GGAAGCCGGGACGAUGUCCGCAUGACAACCGACGUUGGAGUUUGGAGGUGCUUGCCUUAGAGCAAGGGAAACAGCUCUCAUUCAAAGGAACUAGAAGCCUCUCCCUCAGUGGUAGGGAGACAGCCAGGAGCGGUUUUCUGGGAACUGUGGGAUGUGCCCUUGGGGGCCCGAGAAAACAGAAGGAAGAUGCUCCAGACCAGUAACUACAGCCUGGUGCUCUCUCUGCAGUUCCUGCUGCUGUCCUAUGACCUCUUUGUCAAUUCCUUCUCAGAACUGCUCCAAAAGACUCCUGUCAUCCAGCUUGUGCUCUUCAUCAUCCAGGAUAUUGCAGUCCUCUUCAACAUCAUCAUCAUUUUCCUCAUGUUCUUCAACACCUUCGUCUUCCAGGCUGGCCUGGUCAACCUCCUAUUCCAUAAGUUCAAAGGGACCAUCAUCCUGACAGCUGUGUACUUUGCCCUCAGCAUCUCCCUUCAUGUCUGGGUCAUGAACUUACGCUGGAAAAACUCCAACAGCUUCAUAUGGACAGAUGGACUUCAAAUGCUGUUUGUAUUCCAGAGACUAGAGUCAAGAAAACUUUUAAGCUAUUUAUAGCUUUAACAAUUGAGUAUACUCCUAUGAACAAAAUUUGCAGCAUAUUUGUUUUUCUCUGAUUUCUCCAGAAUUUGGAGAUUAUUUGUGAGUAUUCUUUUUUUUUUUUUUUUUUUUUUGAGAUGGAGUUUCACUCUUUUUGCCCAGGCUGGAGUGCAGUGGUGUGAUCUCAGCUCACCACAACCUCUGACUCGCAGGUUCAAACCAUUCUCCUGCCUCAGCCUCCCAAGUAGCUGGGACUACAGGCAUGCGCCACCAUGCCUGGCUAAUUUUUGUAUUUUUAGUAGAGAUGGUGUUUCACUAUGUUGGCCAGGCUGGUCUCAAACUCCUGACCUCAGGCGAUCCACCCACCUCAGCCUCCCAAAGUGCUGGGAUUACAGGCAUUAGCCACUCCACCCAGCUGUGAGUAUUCUUAACUUAUGACAAUACUGUUAUUUGCAUAAGUGCAAUAAGAAUCUGUUUUCGUUUGUAACAGGACACAAUUGGAGAAACUGGUUAUUUUACCAAGGCUUUUACUGGAAUGGUGUGCUUUCCUUUAAGCAAUCAAAUUUGACUUUAUGGAGCCAAUAAAAGCCCCUUGGAAAAACUGGCCCCAUACCUUUGUCCACACAGCCGCUGUCCAAGGUUUCUGACCUGUGGCAAGUAAAGCACGUCACUUUCUGACAGGCCCAGGAGUCCCAAGUUUAUCUUGGAACCUCAAGAGGAGAGGAUCAUGCAAUUCAUAGGUAUUUGAUGGCACAAAUCCACGGCUGGGCUCGGCUUUUAAAAAGUCUUAUCUGAGAUUCUUUCUAUGGAACAAAGUUUCAUCAAAGCCAAUUUAAAAGCCUAUGUAAAAAAUAAUUAUUCGGCCAGAUGCGGUAGCUCAUGCCUAUAAUCCUAGCACUUUGAGAGGCCAAGGCAGGCGGAUCACCUGAGGUCAGGAAUUCAACACCAGCCUGGCCAACAUGGUGAAACCCCAUCCCUACUAAAAAUACAAAAUGUAGCCAGGUGUGAUGGUGCAUGCCUGUAAUUCCAGCUACUCAGGAGGCUGAGGUGGGAUAAUCACUUGAACCCAGGAGGUGGAGGUUGCAGUGAACUGAGAUCACGCCACUGCACUCCAGCCUGGAUGACAGAGCAAGACUCUGUCUCAAAAAAAAAAAUAAUGGAAAACUGGAAAGAGAAAAAUUGUUUCAAAAACUAUAGCACACCUGUUGUUAGAUUCUUGUCUUGCCUAAUGUUUUUCAAUUUUAUUAUUUUCUACAGUUUGGACCGAAUUCUAAUUUUUCUUGACUACAAGUCUUCAAAAUAAUGUUUUCAUUUUUUUCUUCUUUUUUCCAUUUUUUUCCAAUUUGGAGUCACUGAAAACUAAGCUGUGCUUUCAUAAAGCCCUGCAAACUGAAUCUAGACAACUUCAGAAGAAAAAUAACAGCAACCUAUUUACAUACAUAAGCCACUUUCAUACCUGCCUACCGAUGUAUGGACUUCAGAGUAAUGUGGCUUAUAGCAAUUUUCCAGGAUUGUUCUUUUGUUUGUUGUUGUUCUCCCUUCCUCCCCCUAUUUUGUCUUUAUGGGACAUGACACUUCACAACCUUCUAAAAAUGAGUUUUCCUAAUAACUCAGGACCUACUCGUCUAGAAAUAAACCAUCCUAGCCAUGAGAGAUAAGAUAAAA